GCCAAGAGGCAGCAGAGACACUGGCCCACUCUCACGUUCAAAGCAUCUCCGUCCAGCAUGGCCAGGUACAUGCUGCUGCUGCUCCUGGCGGUAUGGGUGCUGACCGGGGAGCUGUGGCCGGGAGCUGAGGCCCGGGCAGCGCCUUACGGGGUCAGGCUUUGCGGCCGAGAAUUCAUCCGAGCAGUCAUCUUCACCUGCGGGGGCUCCCGGUGGAGACGAUCAGACAUCCUGGCCCACGAGGCUAUGGAAAAGAACAUUGAGGCUCCAAGAAGUAAAUUUACUUGCUCACGAUUAGAGAAGCUGGAUUCAUGCUCAGUCAGCCCAGCUCCCAAAUGUACCAGGUCCUCAAUUAAUAAAGAGAGAUACCUUCCCGGAUGCAGAUGCUGAUGAAGACAGUCUGGCAGGCGAGCUGGAUGAGGCCAUGGGGUCCAGCGAGUGGCUGGCCCUGACCAAGUCACCCCAGGCCUUUUACAGGGGGCGACCCAGCUGGCAAGGAACCCCUGGGGUUCUUCGGGGCAGCCGAGAUGUCCUGGCUGGCCUUUCCAGCAGCUGCUGCAAGUGGGGGUGUAGCAAAAGUGAAAUCAGUAGCCUUUGCUAGUUUGAGGGCUGGGCAGCCGUGGGCACCAGGACCAAUGCCCCAGUCCUGCCAUCCACUCAACUAGUGUCUGGCUGGGCACCUGUCUUUCGAGCCUCACACAUUCAUUCAUUCAUCUACAAGUCACAGAGGCACUGUGGGCUCAGGCACAGUCUCCCGACACCACCUAUCCAACCCUGCCCUUUGACCAGCCUAUCAUGACCCUGGCCCCUAAGGAAGCUGUGCCCCUGCCUGGUCAAGUGGGGACCCCCCCAUCCUGACCCCUGACCUCUCCCCAGCCCUAACCAUGCGUUUGCCUGGCCUACACACUCCACUGCCACAACUGGGUCCCUACUCUACCUAGGCUGGCCACACAGAGACCCCUGCCCCCUUCCCAGUCCAAACUGUGGCCAUUGUCCCCUGACCAGCUAAAAUCAAGCCUCUGUCUCAGUCCAGCCUUUGCACGCACGCUUCCUUUGCCCUGCUUUCCAUCCCCUCUCCCUCCAACUCCCCUGCCAGAGUUCCAAGGCUGUGGACCCCAGAGAAGGUGGCAGGUGGCCCCCCUAGGAGAGCUCUGGGCACAUUCGAAUCUUCCCAAACUCCAAUAAUAAAAAUUCGAAGACUUUG